GCGCAUUCUUACCUGUCGGGGUGCGGCGAGUGUCUCACCUCUCUGCACUUCCAAGGACUCUUGUCAUCUGCCUUAGGCGGGAAAUGCUGUUGCUGGAUUGCAACCCCGAGGUGGAUGGUCUGAAGCAUUUGCUGGAGACAGGGGCCUCGGUCAACGCACCCCCGGAUCCCUGCAAGCAGUCGCCUGUCCACUUAGCCGCAGGAAGCGGCCUUGCUUGCUUUCUUCUCUGGCAGCUGCAAACGGGCGCUGACCUCAACCAGCAGGAUGUUUUAGGAGAAGCUCCACUACACAAGGCAGCAAAAGUUGGAAGCCUGGAGUGCCUAAGCCUGCUUGUAGCCAGUGAUGCCCAAAUUGAUUUAUGUAAUAAGAACGGGCAAACAGCUGAAGAUCUCGCUUGGUCAUGUGGAUUUCCAGACUGUGCCAAGUUUCUUACAACAAUUAAAUGUAUGCAGACAAUAAAAGCAAGUGAACACCCUGACAGGAAUGAUUGUGUUGCCGUGCUCAGACAGAAACGGAGUCUCGGAAGUGUAGAAAAUACCAGUGGGAAAAGGAAGUGCUGGUAAGUAACUCAGAGCUGCUGCUUUUUUCCUCCCGCAGUGAUCUCUUGUUUGCAUAGCAUUUAUUAUUCCAUUUAAUACUGACACUCGUAUUUCUAGUAGUAUUGUUUCAUUCUCAUUAACAUUUUAGUACUGGUUAUACUUACCAGAGUCUAGAGACCAAAAAUGGGACUGCAUGGUGGAAGUUUGGGGAUAAAACUCUUUUUAAAAAAAAGUUUUUAAUGUUAACGUGUUUUUAAAAACAGAUGUCACGUGGGUUAUGAAGAAGUCUGAAGAACGCCUUCAUUUCAUGCAAAUCUAUAAGCUCCUGCUUUUGGCUUUACCAUAUGUUGUGUCUAAUCUCCUUCUGAGAAGGACGAAAAACUUUCUUCCAAGUGAAGAUCCAUUUAAGAACACAUGUAUUUACAUGCCUAUAAUAUGCUGGUUGUGUAUGCUUUGUCUUUUAAGUUAUUAAAGGAACGUCUAAAAAAUACAUUCUCCGUGCAGUAUUUACAACCUUUGAAAAAGGUCAUAAUUUAAAUCGUCAAACUAGAACCAGGAUUUAAUGUGAAAAAUUAAACUGAUUCUUUAUUCACAAAUUUAUAAUACCACUCUACUGCAGUCUUUGACUCCAAGAUAUUUUAAAUCAUAUUUGGUCGCUGAGGAAGACAUAAGUUAUAGUAUGCAUCCUUGUUCCAAAAAUCUGGGCCCUUCCAUCCGCACCAGCCCUGGAUAGAGAAGACGGGAAAGGAAAGCCUUUUACAAAGUUACAAGAUUAUGUCAUGGAAAUCGUGACAUCAGGCUCUGUCAGCAGGACCUUGGAAUAAGACUCUAAAUGGCUUUAUCAUUCAAGGAUUUGAAUUCCUACUAGCAUAGAAAAGUAACGUAUCUUACCCUUUAAGGUAGGUUUUUGAACUUUUAAUUCUAUGUAUGUAAUUCAUCAUAAAAAUCAUUAAAAAAAAUUUACCUGUAA